CCCACUUCCCCCGGCUCCAGCCGGCGCAGGCAGCGGCGGCAGCAGCAGGCGAGCCUCGGCCCCGCAAGGCCAUGAAGGUGAAGAAGGGCGGCGGUGGGGCCGGGACGGCGACGGAGUCCGCUCCGGGGCCCUCGGGCCAGAGCGUGGCCCCCAUACCACAGCCGCCUGCGGAAUCCGAAUCUGGGUCCGAGUCGGAGCCGGACGCAGGCCCAGGGCCCAGGCCGGGGCCGCUGCAGAGGAAGCAGCCGAUCGGGCCGGAGGACGUGCUGGGGCUGCAGCGGAUCACCGGUGACUACCUCUGCUCCCCUGAGGAGAAUAUCUACAAGAUCGACUUUGUCAGGUUUAAGAUUCGGGACAUGGACUCAGGCACUGUCCUCUUUGAAAUCAAGAAGCCCCCAGUCUCAGAACGGUUGCCCAUCAACCGGCGGGACCUGGACCCCAAUGCUGGGCGCUUUGUCCGCUACCAGUUCACGCCUGCCUUCCUCCGCCUGAGGCAGGUGGGAGCCACGGUGGAGUUCACAGUGGGAGACAAGCCUGUCAACAACUUCCGCAUGAUCGAGAGGCACUACUUCCGCAACCAGCUACUCAAAAGCUUCGACUUCCACUUUGGCUUCUGCAUCCCCAGCAGCAAGAACACCUGCGAGCACAUUUACGACUUCCCCCCUCUCUCCGAGGAGCUGAGUGCGCGGGCAGGGUCUUCUGGGAGUGGGGAAGUGGGGGCGUCUAGAGACUGAGCUGCGGGAGGGAGAGGGACUUGUGGGUCUGAUCCCAUUUCUCCCCACCCUGGGGCUCUUCUGUGUCUGCCACCAUUCCCAUAUCAUCCGUAGAGAAAGAGGCUGGGGAUAUUUCAGGCUGUUUGGCUGUCCCUGUACCCCAGUCCUGAAGCCCCUGCAGUGGCGGGACUCAAGCUCCUGACCUUUGCCCGGCCUGGCUGGGCCUCUCUUGCAGUCAGCGAGAUGAUCCGCCACCCGUAUGAGACCCAGUCUGACAGCUUCUACUUCGUGGAUGACCGGCUGGUGAUGCACAAUAAAGCAGACUAUUCCUACAGCGGGACACCCUGACCCCACGGCUGCCCUGACCCCAGGAGGCUCCAGUUCUGGGCUGGGAGCUGUGACCUCCCCAACGCUCACCCCUCAACCCCAAGUCCUCUGCUUGGGGAGUUCUCCAGGAGCUCCGGACCCUGAGUCAAUGUUGGGAGGAAGGGUACCUGGUGUCCCCAGUCAAGCCCAUGAAGCCCAUGCGGCCUGCUACAUGGGGUGGGGUCGUAGGGAGGCUGUUUGCCUCCACGUCUAGGAAGGCCUGUGAGAGGAGCAGUCAGGACUUCCGGACAACUUAGCUGGGCCCUACUUGGGCCCAAGUUUCAGAAUAGUGUUCCCCUAUCAAGGCUGUGACUAGAUCAGGCAGGGAUCCAUUCCCUGUCCCCUGCCCACUACCUUCAGGCCAUUUAGAGUUGUAAAUUUACAAAGAUCCACGGUGGGCUCCAGCUGCCAAGCCACCCAAGGGAGUCUGGGCCCUAGGCCUAGCCCCAUCCCUCCCCAUGAGGGGCCAAGACACUGCCUAAGGUGUGGGAGGGACUGGCUGAGAUUGCAGCCCAUGGUAGGAGCUGGACCAACUGUAUAUAGUUUUCAAUAAACUUUUUCCUUUUCUGUUC